GACCCCUGUGGGGCAGAUCAACACUCAAGGCAGGUGCAGAAUCAACAACCUGUGACAAAGCCAGCCAUCCCUGCCAGGAAGCAUGGGGGAUGAGCUGGCACCUUGCCCUGUGGGCACUACAGCUUGGCCGGCCCUGAUCCAGCUCAUCAGCAAGACACCCUGCAUGCCCCAAGCAGCCAGCAACACUUCCUUGGGCCUGGGGGACCUCAGGGUGCCCAGCUCCAUGCUGUACUGGCUUUUCCUUCCCUCAAGCCUGCUGGCUGCAGCCACACUGGCUGUCAGCCCCCUGCUGCUGGUGACCAUCCUGCGGAACCAACGGCUGCGACAGGAGCCCCACUACCUGCUCCCGGCUAACAUCCUGCUCUCAGACCUGGCCUACAUUCUCCUCCACAUGCUCAUCUCCUCCAGCAGCCUGGGUGGCUGGGAGCUGGGCCGCAUGGCCUGUGGCAUUCUCACUGAUGCUGUCUUCGCCGCCUGCACCAGCACCAUCCUGUCCUUCACCGCCAUUGUGCUGCACACCUACCUGGCAGUCAUCCAUCCACUGCGCUACCUCUCCUUCAUGUCCCAUGGGGCUGCCUGGAAGGCAGUGGCCCUCAUCUGGCUGGUGGCCUGCUGCUUCCCCACAUUCCUUAUUUGGCUCAGCAAGUGGCAGGAUGCCCAGCUGGAGGAGCAAGGAGCUUCAUACAUCCUACCACCAAGCAUGGGCACCCAGCCGGGAUGUGGCCUCCUGGUCAUUGUUACCUACACCUCCAUUCUGUGCGUUCUGUUCCUCUGCACAGCUCUCAUUGCCAACUGUUUCUGGAGGAUCUAUGCAGAGGCCAAGACUUCAGGCAUCUGGGGGCAGGGCUAUUCCCGGGCCAGGGGCACCCUGCUGAUCCACUCAGUGCUGAUCACAUUGUACGUGAGCACAGGGGUGGUGUUCUCCCUGGACAUGGUGCUGACCAGGUACCACCACAUUGACUCUGGGACUCACACAUGGCUCCUGGCAGCUAACAGUGAGGUACUCAUGAUGCUUCCCCGUGCCAUGCUCACAUACCUGUACCUGCUCCGCUACCGGCAGCUGUUGGGCAUGGUCCGGGGCCACCUCCCAUCCAGGAGGCACCAGGCCAUCUUUACCAUUUCCUAGAGUUCUUGAGUCCACAGUCUGGCAAGCUGAGGUUAAAAAUCAUAUGUUGAAUGCAGCAGUGUCCACUUAUGACUAACUUCUUAGAACAGCACAAUAUAAUAGUGGAAUUGGGCCUUUCAGAAGACCUCAACUGAUGAUUUU